AUCGCAGUUGCUCCGGAUCUUUGCACACACUCCACGGGCAGUUGGAGGUGAGCUGCUGCCGGCCACGCCAGAGGCUGCAACACCAGACAUGGAUGGGUGCAAAAAAGAGCUGCCCCGCUUGCAAGAGCCGGAGGAGGACGAGGAUUGUUACAUCCUUAAUGUUCAGUCAAGCAGUGAUGACACCAGUGGGUCUUCUGUGGCCAGAAGAGCUCCGAAGAGACAGGCGAGUUGCAUCCUUAAUGUCCAGUCAAGGAGUGGUGACACCAGUGGGUCUUCUGUGGCCAGAAGAGCUCCGAAGAGACAGGCGAGCUCCGUGGUAGUGAUUGACUCUGAUUCUGAUGAGGAAUGUCACACCCAUGAAGAGAAGAAAGCUAAGUUAUUGGAAAUAAACAGCGACGAUGAGAGUCCGGAGUGUUGUCAUGUGAAGCCUGCCAUCCAGGAACCUCCAAUAGUUAUUAGUGAUGAUGACAAUGACGAUGACAACGGUAAUGAUUUGGAAGUUCCCGACGACAACAGUGAUGAUUCAGAAGCUCCCGACGACAACAGUGAUGAUUCGGAAGCUCCUGACGACAACAGUGAUGAUUCGGAAGCUCCCGACGACAACAGUGAUGAUUCGGAAGCUCCCGACGACAAUAGUGAUGAUUCGGAUGUUCCCGACGACAACAGUGAUGAUUCAUCCGACGACAACAGUGAUGAUUCAUCCGACGACAACAGUGAUGAUUCGGAUGUUCCCGACGACAAGAGUGAUGAUUCGGAUGUUCCCGACGACAGCAGUGAUGAUUCGGAUGUUCCCGACGACAGCAGUGAUGAUUCGGAAGCUCCCGACGACAGCAGUGAUGAUUCGGAAGCUCCCGACGACAGCAGUGAUGAUUCGGAAGCUCCCGACGACAGCAGUGAUGAUUCGGAAGCUCCCGACGACAGCAGUGAUGAUUCGGAAGCUUCCGACGACAGCAGUGAUGAUUCGGAAGCUUCCGACGACAGCAGUGAUGAUUCGGAAGCUCCCGACGACAAGAGUGAUGAUUCGGAUGUUCCCGAAGACAAGAGUGAUGAUUCGGAUGUUCCCGAUGACAAUAGUGAUGAUUUGGAAGUUCCUGUGCCAGCAGAAGAUUUGUGUAAUGAAGGCCAAAUUGCUUCAGAUGAAGAAGAGCUGGUUGAGGCUGCUGCUGCUGUCUCCCAGCAUGAUUCAUCUGAUGAUGCUGGUGAGCAGGAUCUUGGUGAGAAUCUCAGCAAACCACCAAGUGAUCCUGAGGCUAACCCUGAAGUUUCAGAGAGAAAGCUGCCAACUGAGGAAGAGCCUGCACCUGUGGUGGAACAAUCAGGGAAAAGGAAGUCAAAAACCAAAACUAUUGUGGAGCCACCGAGGAAAAGGCAGACAAAGACCAAAAAUAUAGUGGAGCCACCAAGGAAAAGGCAGACAAAGACCAAAAAUAUAGUGGAGCCACUGAGGAAGAGGAAGGCGAAAACCAAAAAUGUAUCUGUGACACCUGGACAUAAGAAGCGUGGGCCUUCAAAGAAGAAACCCGGUGCAGCAAAAGUUGAAAAACGCAAGACUAGGACUCCUAAAUGCAAAGUCCCUGGAUGUUUCUUGCAAGACCUUGAAAAGUCAAAGAAAUACUCUGGAAAAAAUUUAAAGCGAAAUAAGGAUGAAUUGGUUCAGAGAAUCUACGACCUGUUUAACAGAUCCGUCUGUGAUAAAAAGCUGCCAGAGAAACUACGCAUAGGCUGGAAUAACAAGAUGGUGAAAACUGCUGGCUUAUGCAGCACUGGUGAGAUGUGGUACCCAAAGUGGCGGCGCUUUGCCAAGAUCCAGAUUGGCUUGAAAGUCUGCGACUCUGCAGACCGAAUCCGGGAUACCUUGAUCCAUGAAAUGUGCCAUGCUGCCUCCUGGCUGAUUGAUGGUAUCCAUGAUUCUCAUGGUGACGCAUGGAAGUAUUAUGCCAGGAAAUCCAACAGGAUACACCCGGAGCUGCCCAGGGUCACCCGUUGCCAUAACUAUAAGAUUAACUACAAGGUCCAUUAUGAAUGUACUGGAUGCAAAACGAGGAUUGGCUGCUACACCAAAUCGUUGGACACCAGCCGCUUCAUCUGUGCCAAAUGCAAGGGGUCUCUGGUCAUGGUGCCAUUAACUCAGAAAGAUGGGACCCGUAUUGUGCCCCACGUGUGACCAUUUGCUGUGUAUGUGCAGAAGUAUUAUAGAAAAAUUAUGCAGGAGAUGGCUAGGAUUAGCCUUGGGGAUGUGAUGAAAACACUUGGCAGGAAUUACAAGGCAAUGAAGAAUUCUUAAGGUUAUCUUAGAGUAUAUUAAUGUGAGCUAUAUCCUUUACUGGUAAGAAGUUUUAGAAAAGUUUGUUUUGUGAAGUUAGGAAUAUUAGAAUUUAGGUACUGUUAAGUAAGUAAUGUUAGAAUUUAAGAUUCAUGUUAUUAACGAUGAUUGACCUUAAAUAGGGACUCUAUUGCUAACCAUUCUGUGCCCUUGACAGGGUAUUUCUGAAGCCCUUGGGAUCUACCUUGGGUCUUACUUGAGUUCCAUAUUUUUCACAUGUAGAACAAAAUGCAAAAGAAAAGUGAGUUUUCAAGAGUGGCAGGUUGAGAGAGGAGAAUGCUGGAAAGAGGACAAGUUUGAGAGGCAACACUUAAACACUAGGGCUACUGUGGCAUCUAUGUAGACAGGAAAGACAAACGUGUUUCAUAAAAUUCGUUGUUGAUGGUAUUGAUUGAAACUAUCUGAGCCAUGUAAUCAAAAAAUAAAAGUUUUCUGCAUCUUG